GUCAGUCGAGGAGUCAAGGCAGCAAUGAAUCGUGUCUUGUGUGCCCCGGCGGCCGGGGCCGUCCGGGCGCUGAGGCUCAUAGGCUGGGCUUCCCGAAGCCUUCAUCCGUUGCCCGGUUCCCGGGAUCGGGCCCACCCUGCCGCCGAGGAAGAGGACGACCCUGACCGCCCCAUUGAGUUUUCCUCCAGCAAAGCCAACCCUCACCGCUGGUCGGUGGGCCAUACCAUGGGAAAGGGACAUCAGCGGCCCUGGUGGAAGGUGCUGCCCCUCAGCUGCUUCCUCGUGGCGCUGAUCAUCUGGUGCUACCUGAGGGAGGAGAGCGAGGCGGACCAGUGGUUGAGACAGGUGUGGGGAGAGGUGCCAGAGCCCAGUGAUCGUUCUGAGGAGCCUGAGACUCCAGCUGCCUACAGAGCGAGAACUUGACGGGGUGCCCGCUGGGGCUGGCAGGAAGGGAGCCGACAGCCGCCCUUCGGAUUUGAUGUCACGUUUGCCCGUGACUGUCCUGGCUAUGCGUGCGUCCUCAGCACUGAAGGACUUGGCUGGUGGAUGGGGCACUUGGCUAUGCUGAUUCGCGUGAAGGCGGAGCAGAAUCUCAGCAGAUCGGAAACUGCUCCUCGCCUGGCUCUUGAUGUCCAAGGAUUCCAUCGGCAAGACUUCUCAGAUCCUUGGGGAAGGUUUCAGUUGCACUGUAUGCUGUUGGAUUUGCCAAGUCUUUGUAUAACAUAAUCAUGUUUCCAAAGCACUUCUGGUGACACUUGUCAUCCAGUGUUAGUUUGCAGGUAAUUUGCUUUCUGAGAUAGAAUAUCUGGCAGAAGUGUGAAACUGUAUUGCAUGCUGCGGCCUGUGCAAGGAACACUUCCACAUGUGAGUUUUACACAACAACAAAUGAAAAUAAAUUUUAAUUUUAUAAUAUGGGA